GCGCUGCUCGCACCCCGGGACCCGCCCGGGCUGCCGGCUGAUGUGGACCGUCCGACCCGCGUGUCUGAUAAUCCUUUGACGGGUUUUGGUCGGCGGAGAAUGGUCUCUAAACUUCCCAAACCGCCCCCGUUUCACGUCCUGUGAAAGGAAGUGCUCCUCUGAUGACCAAUCAGCGGCGAGAAGCUCUUUUAACGUCCGUCCUUCUUUCACGCCUCCUUCCCCGCGCUUUGGUUCGUGCGUCCGCGCCCCAGUGUCGGGUCUGCGUGGAUCGGUCCUUCCAGGACACCGUCGCCUUCCCGGCCGCGUCGGAGUCCGGCGGCGACCUGCCUCUGAAACAUGGCAGGCUCGGAUGCUGGUGAGUGUCUCCCUGGGGUCCCAGUAUGUGUGGACUGAAACCGUCCACCUCCAGGGAGGCCUCGGGCUAGCCCGGACUGGGUCUGGGCUGUCGGCGGGGCUCGUGACCUUCAGACGCCGCGUCGCGCUGGCGGGUUCCCUGGAUAGGGUCUCUCAGCUUCACCACCUCUUCGCUUCGAGGCCGUGGAACAGCAGUAUGCUGUGGGAGAGAGAGAGGCACUGGGGCGAGGCCGGUAGGACACUUGGGUCCUGGCUGUAAAAAGAGCGGUCAGAAGGGUCGUCCCCGGACUUGUCUUUCUGUGGGGCGUCUAGCCGCUGUCCGUGUGCCCUCCGCCCUUGCACUAUGGGCCCUGAGGUCGUACCUGCUUUUGUAUUGGUCUUUAAAGGAACAGCAUUCUUAAGAUUUAUUAUGCCCCUGCAGAAUAGUAGAAUAUGCCCCUGUAGAAUAGUUGUGCUUUUUUCUCUUCAGUGCCCUCUAGAGUCAUGGGCUUUGUCUAGCACCGCUUUUGAAGAGCGAAUUAAUUUGGUUGUCUAGGACGCUUUCAUCCUUUUCACAAGGACUGCGUACAAACCAGUUGUCAUGGUUUGGCCAGCUGUGAGAAAUGGGCGUGGGGAGGGGGAUUAUGUGCAUGGAAAAUACACUCUCAUUCGUUUCCAGAACGUUACGUGUCCAGAACAUAGUGGAGAUGUUUGUUUCUAAUACCGAUUGAAAGUGCUUUCCUACCAAUUCCCAGGCAUUUCAAGGAACAAGUAUUUUAAGCUAAGUUACUUUUGGUACAGAAACCGUUAAACUUUGCAAAUCCCAGCAAUAUCUAGGGGAGAGGAGAAUGUGGUACGCAGGAAACGUCAACAGUAUUGAUAAUUCUGAGCUUCAUGUACUUCCCAUAUUUUCUUUCAUAUAGAUCGAUAUAAUAAAAAAGAAAAACUAACAAAUGCAUUACCGUUGAUGUUGUUAUUAUACCAGUUCUUAACAGCCUAAGUUUAAUCACCACUUUUUCCGGCACCAGAGAAACCCUGACUUGCACAAGAUAAUUGGGUAAACACAAGACCAAUACUAUUGCAAGUGCGAAGCAGCCUCCAUUAAUGAGUUUCUGGUAACCUCGGAUUAUCAUUAAACUGUUGUUUAUGACAUAAUAUUCCUGUUUACUUGUAAAUAUGUUUUAACUAAAAACACCCAUGUAAGGCUUAUAUAAGUAACUUAAGAUUUUAGGCUGCAACAGUAUCAAUUGAAUUUGCAGUAUAGUUUUGACUAUGUAGAAAUUACAGCACUCUGGAAAUCAUCCCAAGAAAUUAAAUACAUCUUUUUAAAAACCAUGCCUAAAGGGUCUUUGAAAUUCUCUAACAAUCAAAUUCCUUAUCUUCUGCAAAGUUCAGUGUCUGUUUUUGUUGGGGGGGAGGUUGUUGGAUUUUUUAAAUGUCUGUGUGAUUUUUUUCUGGUGGUUUUUAAGACUGAUCUUUCCCCCUUUUUCCCAACAGAGUGGGUAACCAUUGCCAAUAACCUUCUUUUUAAGUGUCAUAUACAUCUGAGAAUACAUGAACUUCAAGACUGUGAUGCUAAUGUUUUUAUUGCUCUUUAUCAGUCUAUUUUGGGAGAAAAGGUACCAGACCUCAUAGUUAUUCCUAGGAGUCAAGAAGAUGAUGCACACAAUGUACAAGCAGUAAUUGAUUCACUGGCCUUGGACUACUUGCAGGUCAGCUUGUCUCACAUAACAGGAGAAAAUAUAGUGAAAGGAGAUAAAGAAUCUAUUAAGAAUCUCCUGGAAAUAUUUGAUGGUUUGUUGGAGUAUCUUACAGAACGCAUCAGUGAAACAUCUCAUGAGAAAAGUGAAACUGAACAGUAUUUUAAAGAAUCUGAUCGAGGAGAACGUUUGGAAGAGCCAGAAAGUACUAAAGAAUCUAAAUCAUCAUGGAAAAGAGUUUCUUUUGGGAGGUGCUCCUUGUCUUCUGAGAUGUUGGGCCCCUCUUGGGAUGGAGAUGAAGCAGAAUCCACUGGUGAAAUCAUUAGACUUGGAGACACAGCACACACCUUUUCUCUAAGAAGUAAUGGUGCUCAAUGUCCUAAUGAAAUGCUGUCUAAAAAAGCCUUAGCCUCACCAAGUUCUAAAUCACAUGAAGAUAUGUUGUACCCUCCUAGUGUUUUGUCCAAGAGUAGGACAUCCUUUGUUGAAGACACGGAAACCCUUUCUGUGAGUGGGAUUCCAAAUGCUAGGAAGCUAGGGGAGCCUAUCCGAGCAGCUAUUCCUUUACAUCCACCCUACCACCCUUCAGAGCCUCGAGCACCCUGCCCCAUAGGAAAAGAAUACUUGCAUUCAAGUCACUGCUCCCCAGCCGUAAAUUCUACUGGAGAGCAUACGGAAUUUUCUGGGGAUCUAGAUGAUGGACUUUUCUUAAUUUCCAAGUUGCCUAAAGGCAGCAAAUGGGAAGUAUAUCCAGCUCAGGUCCAAGGGCCUAGGACAAGGAAGCCUCCCAAAGGAAAAAGAAAUGAAAACAGAGCUACAGCCUCAUCCUGCAAUUCACCUUUCCCCCAGAGGCCAAGAAAGAGAUUAACAGAACAAGAAUUACAUGAUGUAUCAGAAAAACUCUCUCAGCGGCUUUCUGAACUAGAUUGGGACUUUCCAUGCGUAGAAAGCCACCCUACAGAUCCCAUUCGCUCUCUCCAUCUCCAGUUAACAAACACAAACAGUUCCACUUGGAGAGAAAAAGGCAGCGCAAGCCAAGAGAAACAGAUGUCCGCCAAUUCCAAGCACAGGCGUUUACUGAAGCAUUUGAAAGGGAACUAAGAAGACAUAAAGUUCAAGAGAAUAUUGGACCUCUAAGAAUACAUGAGAAGGAGGAGGAAACAGUGGGUAAAAGUCUCCACUGUAAUAAAUGCCAUUUGAUCAGAUGAGUGGGAAGUACAAAGAUGAUCUUUUUAAAAGAAGAAGGGGCCAACAGGGCCUUAAUCAUGAGCUCUUUAGGAAAAGGCAGGAUUUCAUGUCAUGAUACAGGACUUGCUUAUUAAUAAGGCAUUCAGGUUGCUAAAAUAUGACGAGACAUGGUUCCAAAGAAAAGUAGUGUUUUUCCGCUACUUAAAACUUCCCAUCAGUUUUUAAGGGUUUAUUUGACUUAGCAGUUCACCAGGGGCUUAAAAACUACUCUAGGCUGACAAAAUUAAAGAAGAGUAAGAGAAGACAGAACAUCCUAGUUGGCUAUAGACCUGGUUGUAAGAAACCCAAAACAGAAGUUUUCAUUGCCUUUCAAAAGAAUGGUUACAGAAACUAAGUGAAAUCAUGGGGAAAAUGCUUAUGCUAAAAUAUUCAUGAACAAAACAGGAUAUAAAGUACAGUAUGGUUACAACUAAGCAUACUGCAUAGUUGCCUGAGAAUUUUUUAAAUCUACAUGGAAAAAGAGAAGUACAUUGAAACAUUAAUGGUUAAAAAAAAGAUUAAUAGUGGUUGUAUUUAGGGUGUGGGACUAUGGUGACUGAAACUUGAAAAAGAUUCAGUGCUUUUUCAAAUUCCAAGGGAUGCCAGAGGCCAAAAGGUGCAUUUAACUUAGAGUAAAUGAAUAUUAACCAGAUUUUACAAAUUUGAAGUAAGGUGGUUUGGCUUACUGUUAGCUAAAAAACUAAAAAACUACCGUUAGCUGUUUUUGUCAGUAUGUAAUAUUUAAGAUGAUGUAUGAAAGAACUGUUAGACCUUUUAUUUUUAUUCUGUUUUAUAUCUGCUUCUAAGGAAAAAAUAUACAGAGGAGAAGCUGUUCGUAAAGGAACUCCAGAAUGUAGUCAGCCCUGGAAGAUUUACUCUAGAAAAACCACAACGCAGAGUCUAAGAGGUGGCCUCCCAAAGCCAAAUAAAGCAGUUCCAAGUAAGAACCACAGAAUUGUACUUUAUGGAAAACUGGCAACCUUUGAAAGCAUGUGCAACAUUCCAAGGACACAGCACUGAAAGCUAACAUCCACCAGUUAGCCGAAGAAAGUUUUUUUUUUUUCCCAAUCACUGCCAUGUGGCUGGUUUUCCGUAGAGGGCUAAAACUCUUCAAUAAGGAAGUACUUCAGGGAGGCCUAUAUAUUGGCACCCAAGGAAUGCCAGGACUGCCACCUGCUGCUCCAGCGUUAGCCUCACUCGUGUGCUUACUCACUUUGACUGCCUUUUUGUCUAUUUCUGGGAGGUUGGUAGAAUGAAAGGGAUGCUCCAAGGCAAGCAGAUGGCCUGUCCACCUCCUAUAUAUUGACAGUGCCAAUGAGUGUAGAGUCUUGUUACAAGAAACAAAGUCAUGAGAAAUGCCAGGCUUCCUGUUACACCCAAAGACUGCUGGCCCUCCUACUCUAUCCUUUAGACCAGAAACUUUUUCUUCUAAGCACUUGCCUACCGGGAAGGUUGAGGAGUCUUGUUUUACCGUACGUAGAGAAUCUACCCACAGGCACUGAAGCGGCUGAGCAAUUAGGAUGGACUUCCCAGGACCAGCAUGGCAUCAAUCCAGAACUAUUGAGCUUAUUUUUAUCCUUACCAGUAGUUGGCUUACUCCAAUCAGAGGAGUAAUGCAAAUUAUUAUAAGUACAUUUAGAAUUGUUCUUUUCAGGAUCAAAACCACAUCACUUACAUAAGCUUUGAUCUACCAGGGAUGUUGGAUGACAGUUCUUGUCCACGUCUCAGAUUAAGAACAUCUUAUUUUACCUUGCAGUGAAAGUAAGUGAACACAGUCUCCUGCCCCUUAUGCUGGAGCAGUUUCCGUUUCUUUAUGUUUCUGGCCCAACACUAAGCAAAAUGUGGAAACAGCAAAUUGCACAGGUUGAACAGCUUAAGAAAGAAGCAUGUAGAGAAAAUCGAUCAAA